GUUCCUCCUGGUUUUCUCCUGCCUCGUGCUGUCUGUGUUUUCCACCAUCAAGGAGUAUGAGAAGAGCUCGGAGGGGGCCCUCUACAUCCUGGAAAUCGUGACUAUCGUGGUGUUUGGCGUGGAGUACUUCGUGCGGAUCUGGGCCGCAGGCUGCUGCUGCCGGUACCGUGGCUGGAGGGGGCGGCUCAAGUUUGCCCGGAAACCGUUCUGUGUGAUUGACAUCAUGGUGCUCAUCGCCUCCAUUGCGGUGCUGGCCGCCGGCUCCCAGGGCAACGUCUUUGCCACAUCUGCGCUCCGGAGCCUGCGCUUCCUGCAGAUUCUGCGGAUGAUCCGCAUGGACCGGCGGGGAGGCACCUGGAAGCUGCUGGGCUCUGUGGUCUAUGCCCACAGCAAGGAGCUGGUCACUGCCUGGUACAUCGGCUUCCUUUGUCUCAUCCUGGCCUCGUUCCUGGUGUACUUGGCAGAGAAGGGGGAGAACGACCACUUUGACACCUACGCGGAUGCACUCUGGUGGGGCCUGAUCACGCUGACCACCAUUGGCUACGGGGACAAGUACCCCCAGACCUGGAACGGCAGGCUCCUUGCGGCAACCUUCACCCUCAUCGGUGUCUCCUUCUUCGCGCUGCCUGCAGGCAUCUUGGGGUCUGGGUUUGCCCUGAAGGUUCAGGAGCAGCACAGGCAGAAGCACUUUGAGAAGAGGCGGAACCCGGCAGCAGGCCUGAUCCAGUCGGCCUGGAGAUUCUACGCCACCAACCUCUCGCGCACAGACCUGCACUCCACGUGGCAGUACUACGAGCGAACGGUCACCGUGCCCAUGUACAGUUCGCAAACUCAAACCUACGGGGCCUCCAGACUUAUCCCCCCGCUGAACCAGCUGGAGCUGCUGAGGAACCUCAAGAGUAAAUCUGGACUCGCUUUCAGGAAGGACCCCCCGCCGGAGCCGUCUCCAAGUAAAGGCAGCCCGUGCAGAGGGCCCCUGUGUGGAUGCUGCCCCGGACGCUCUAGCCAGAAGGUCAGUUUGAAAGAUCGUGUCUUCUCCAGCCCCCGAGGCGUGGCUGCCAAGGGGAAGGGGUCCCCGCAGGCCCAGACUGUGAGGCGGUCACCCAGCGCCGACCAGAGCCUCGAGGACAGCCCCAGCAAGGUGCCCAAGAGCUGGAGCUUCGGGGACCGCAGCCGGGCACGCCAGGCUUUCCGCAUCAAGGGUGCCGCGUCACGGCAGAACUCAGAAG